AGACCGCCUGUUAUGGCGGCCGCCUAAGUCCCACAGAGACGGGAGUCGGGUGGGAUCCCAGGCUGGGCCCCGCGGCGGCUUUUGCUGCCCCACAGCAACCACUUAAAUGUAGGAACUCCAGCAGUGUACUGGGAUCAUUAGGACAGCCUGAGUCAUGAUGACCUCAUUUUGCAGUUGAAGAAGUGGGGGCCCUGAAGAUUUCAUGACAUCUACCCAGGUAGGAACAGCUCCUAUAGGCAGUCAGGGGUUACAGGCAGGUUUGGGUCAAAUACCUGAAACCAACCCCAGGACAAGGAGGUUGCUGGUGUUUUAUUAACACCUACUGUGAGCCAAGGACUCUGCUCAGCAGUUUACCCACCCAGUAACACUGCGUGAGAUUGUGGCUGAAGAAACAGAUGCAGAGAGGCGAAGUGAUUUUCCUGAAAUCACAUGGCUAGAAGCUGGAUUCUCUUCCCUGGCCAAGUCUCUGAGAUCUUCUCCCAGGGCGAUGCAAAGCUACUCGCUACCAGCUUGGACCUGUCUGCAGUAUCUCCUCUGGGACCUGCCAUGCUGAGGACCCAUUCUCACCUCUGAGGGACUCCUGUCCUAGGACUAAGGUGGAGCCUGGGCCAUGGUACAGCUGGCUCCUGCGGCAGCCAUGGACGAGGUCACCUUUAGGAGCGACACUGUGCUGUCAGAUGUCCACCUCUAUACCCCGAACCAUAGACAUCUCAUGGUACGGCUGAACAGCGUGGGGCAGCCAGUUUUCCUGUCCCAAUUCAAGCUUCUAUGGAGCCAAGACUCUUGGACAGAUUCAGGAGCCAAGGGUGGCAGUCACAGAGAUGUUCACACAAAGGAGCCUCCUUCUGCUGAGACAGGCAGCACAGGGUCCCCUCCAGGAAGUGGCCAUGGUAAUGAGGGUUUCUCCCUCCAGGCCGGGACUGACACCACUGGCCAGGAAGUGGCUGAAGCUCAGCUGGAUGAGGAUGGGGAUUUGGACGUGGUGAGAAGACCACGAGCCGCCUCUGAUUCCAACCCAGCAGGGCCUCUGAGAGACAAGGUACAUCCCAUGAUUCUAGCACAGGAAGAAGACGACGUCCUGGGAGAGGAAGCACAAGGCAGCCCGCACGAUAUCAUCAGAAUAGAGCACACCAUGGCCACGCCCCUGGAGGAUGUUGGCAAGCAGGUGUGGCGGGGCGCCCUGCUCCUGGCAGACUACAUCCUGUUCCGACAGGACCUCUUCCGAGGAUGUACAGCGCUGGAGCUCGGGGCCGGCACGGGGCUCGCUAGCAUCAUCGCAGCCACCAUGGCACGGACCGUUUAUUGUACAGAUGUCGGUGCAGAUCUCUUGUCCAUGUGCCAGCGAAACAUUGCCCUCAACAGCCACCUGGCUGCCACUGGAGGUGGUAUAGUUAGGGUCAAAGAACUGGACUGGCUGAAGGACGACCUCUGCACAGAUCCCAAGGUCCCCUUCAGUUGGUCACAAGAGGAAAUUUCUGACUUGUACGAUCACACCACCAUCCUGUUUGCAGCCGAAGUGUUUUACGACGACGACUUGACUGAUGCUGUGUUUAAAACGCUCUCCCGACUCGCCCACAGAUUGAAAAAUGCCUGCACAGCCAUACUGUCGGUGGAGAAGAGGCUCAACUUCACAUUGAGACACUUGGACGUCACAUGUGAAGCCUACGAUCACUUCCGCUCCUGCCUGCACGCGCUGGAGCAGCUCGCAGAUGGCAAGCUGCGCUUCGUGGUGGAGCCCGUGGAGGCCUCCUUCCCACAGCUCCUGGUUUACGAGCGCCUCCAGCAACUGGAGCUCUGGAAGAUCAUCGCAGAACCAGUAACAUGACCCAUCGCCUCCACAAGGCGCGGCGUCUCGACUGUUCUUAGAGUGUAUUUCUAGUAAAAUCAGAAGCUCACCAAAGCAACAUGCUUGAGAUUUUGUCAUUUUAAAAAUAUGGUUACACGUACCUUAGAUGACCCAAGAUGGUUUUCUGGGGUCUGUCCCUGCCUCCCAGUUGUAGCCAGAGAAGGUUGUUGCUGUGGGCUGGAGGUCACUUUAGUUGCCUGUUUCUCAUGGUUGUGAUGUGUGCUCCAGGGUCAAGCCGAGCCACGUUCCUUCUCAGCUCAGUUCCACCCACGUCAGUCAUUUCAGCUGUGUGCUUUACUUGCGGUUGCGGCCCUGGCUGUGAGGUGGAUUCUUGUACUGCCCUCUGUCAGCUGUUUACAGAUGGGUUGACUACCACUGCCAGUAUUGCCAUCAUAUUGCCGCUCGGCACAAAAGCCUCAUUUCCUCCCAGGGUUGGGUAUGCUCCACCCCAUCACUCUGGUGAGGGCCCCAUGAGAAGGAAGAGGCAGGAGCUGGCGCCAGGAAUGGACUGGCAUUGGCCUUUGUAUUUAAUUUUAACUCUUUAUCACCCAAAUCAGGUACGUUUGGAAUAAACCUAAGAGCCACUCUUUGGGGUCAUGUGCAGCUGACCAGGGUUUGUGCAGUGAUCUUCCUCAGAGGUGUUCCCUUCCGCCUGGACUCAUUUUCCCUCCGCCCCUUGGUCUCUCUGUCUUAUCACGUGUGUACAUGUCUGUCUGUCUGGUUUUUUAUCUUCUCCAUCUGUGCCUCUCUCCUCCCAUCUCCACCCCUUCCUGUCAUCCUCUAUGUCCCACUGUCUCUCUCCUUCUCUCCAGUUUUGGUCCCAUCUUCCUGCUACCCUUGGCCCUCCCUGCAGCCCCUUUCCCCUGCCUUGCUGCUGCCGCACACUUUGCACCAGGGCCUUUCAUGGCCCCUUUCCGCCUCCCUUGCAGCUCAGGUUUCCUGGCUUCUCCAUGCACUGUCCCUGCCCACACUCGCUUCUCCCCAAGCUCCCAGGUUCCAUCCCUAGGCCCAUCAUACCCCUGGCAUUGGCUAAUCCCUCAUGCCAGGGGCCAGGCACUUGCAAGUCUAACUUCAUCUUCCCAACAAAUUUAGGAGGUCCGCAGCCUUGUGAUACCCACAUUACAGCGGAGAAGACUGAGGUCCAAAAAGGAAAAAGUCUCCAUGAGGUCAGGGACCUUGUUUGUCUUAAAUAUCACUACAUCCCUGCUGUAUGGUCUGGCAAACAGUAGAUGCUCAACACAUAUUGUUGAAUGAAUUGCUAAUGUAAGUUACUAAUUAGGUCAUUAUUUCCUAUUUGUGAGUGAUUUUGCCUCCAGGAACAUUUGGCAGUGCCUGGAGACAUUUUCGGUGGUCACAAGUAGGGGAGACGGGUGCCACCAGUAUCCAGUGGGUGAGGCCAGAGAUGCUGCUGAACGUUCUAUAAUGCGGUAAUCACGGAGCAUCCCCCACAACACAAAAUGAUCCAGCCCAAAAUGUGAGUAGCGCCGAGGCGGAGAAAUCCUGACUUGGAAGAAGAAAGCCAAGUACUUUAGAGAAGAAAAACGGUCUCAGCUGAACCUGUAGUGAGAGCAUGCAGGAGAGUGACCUCACCCUGCCCCUCUGGGAGCAAGAAGAAAACCUAUGCAUGUACGUUAUUAUAAAUCUUCAAAGAACCUAAAAGGCAGAAGUGAUCCCUAUUUUGCACAUGAGAAAUCCAAAAUUCAGAGAGGUUCAGCAACUUGCCCAACAUCACACAGCAACCAAGGGCAGAGUCAGGUUUAGAGCCCAUGUCCACCCAUGUCCAUCUGACUCCUGAGCCUGUGCUUUUCCCACAUUCCCGCUGGAGCAGCAGCAGCAUCUGUGGCAUCACGUGGAUGCUGGUUAGAAAUGCAACAUCAGGCUGAGCAUGUUGGCUCACUCCUGCAAUCCCGAUACUUUGGGAGGCCAAGGCAGGAGGAUCAAUUAAGGCCAGGAGUUCAACCAGCCUGGACAACAAAGCAAGACCCCAUCUCUAUUAAAAAUUAAACAGCCAAUUAGUCUGGCAUGGUGGUUUGCGCCUGCAGUCCCAGCUACUUGGGAGGCCGAGGCAGGAGAAUCGCUUGAACCUGGGAGGCGAAGGUUGCAGUGAGCCAAGAUCGCAACACUGCCCUCCAGCCUGGGCAACAGAGCCAGACAUCUCAAAAAUUAAAAAGCCAGGCGAGGUGCCGGGCAUGGUGGCUCAUGCCUGUCAUCCCAGCACUUUGGGAGGCCGAGGCGGGUGGAUCACCCAAAGUCAGGAGUUCAAGACCAGCCUGGCCAACAUGGUGAAACCCUGCCUCUACUAAAAAUACAAAAUUAGCCGGGUGUGGUGGCUCAUGCCUGUAAUCCCAGCUACUUGGGAGGCUGAGGCAGGAGAAUCACUUGAACCCAGGAGGCAGAGGUUGCAGUGAGCCAAGACCAUGCCAUUGCACUCUAGCCUGGGCAACAAGAGCAAAACUCCAUCUCAAAAAAAAAAAAAAGCCAGGCGUAGUGGCUAACGCCUGUAGUCCCAACUACUCAGAAGGCAAGGUGAGAGGAUUGCUUGAGCCUAAGAAUUUGAGGCUGCAGUGAGCCAUGACUGCACCAUUGCACUCUGGCCUGGGCAACAGAGAGAGAUCCUGUCUCCAAAAAAGAAGAAAAGUAUCAAGCCUCAGCUCAGGACGUGAUUCCGAAUCUGCAUCUCAACGAGACCCUGGGUGAUUUGUGUGCACAGUAGUUUGAGAAGCUCUGGGGCCUACCACAUAGCCCUCAACCUAUUGCUGUUUUCUAAAAUUCCUACACAAACUCCGUUCCUGACAGACUUGCCAUAAUGGAGCAGCAUUGCAGAUCACUACAGGGAAUAUUAAUAAUGAGUCUUCAAAUCAGAACCCCACUAGACAGAGCCAACAACUGGCAGUACGUCAGCACUAAUGGUGACAAUUUCCUAGCACUCCUGGGUACAAGUCCAUAAAUGUAAUUGGCACCAAGCAAUAGAGUUGUCACAGCUUUCACCUGCCGCAUUAGGGCAAACUGCUUUUAUGUCUAAACCACUGGGCCUGAAAGCUUCCUCUAAGUAGAGCCUGGAAUUAAUCUUGAUCCACUGUAAUUCAAAGUAUCGUCAGAUUUUCAUUUCCCAGAGUGGGAGCGCGCCCCCAUUGCCAUGUUUUAUGGCCUUGUUUGAGCCUCUACAAGUGCUUGUUUGGCAGCGAUAUUCAGAAUCACCAAACCAUGGGGAUGUUCUGCUAGGUAAUUAGCCCAGGCCAGUGGACUCAAUUUUUUUAUAACAUUUUCAGAAAAAUAUGUGACCCAAGGAGGGGACUUGGCUGUUCAGCUGCAGCCUGCAUGGGAAAGAACUGUUAAAACCAACAAAGCCAGGCACAGUGGCUCACACCUGUAAUUCCAGCAUUUUGGGAGGCCGAGGUGGGUGGAUCACCUAAGGUCAGGAGUUCGAGACCAGCCUGGCCAACAUGGUGAAACCCCGUCUCUACUAAAAAUACAAAAAAAAAAAAAAAAA